AAGGAAAUCCCAAUCUCUAUUCCGAAGAGUCUUCCCUAAAAGAUGGCCCUGAUCAGGAAGACAUUUUAUUUUCUAUUUGCUAUGUUCUUCAUUUUGGUUCAACUGCCAUCAGGGUGCCAGGCAGGACUUGAUUUUUCCCAACCAUUUCCAUCAGGUGAGUUUGCUGUCUGUGAGUCGUGCAAGCUUGGUCGGGGAAAAUGCAGGAAGGAGUGCUUGGAGAAUGAGAAGCCCGAUGGAAAUUGCAGGCUGAACUUUCUCUGCUGCAGACAGAGGAUCUGACAAACCAGACCAGCACACUUCUGGCCUUAGAAGCAGACCUGGAUAUUCAAAGAAGUUCAAGAGAAGUUAUGUGGCUUAUCCAAAUCACACAGUGAGUGAGUCUCAGAAUCAUUCUCAUUUCUUUCUCCCUUUGUUACGUUUUAUUGCUUAUUUUUUAAAGAUGACUUUUUUUCUUUUUUUUUUUUUUUGAGAAGGAGUCUCACUCUGUCGCCCAGGCUGGAGUGCAGUGGCUCGAUCUUGGCUCACUGCAACCUCCACCUCCCGGGUUCAAGCAAUUCUCCUGCUUCAGCCUCCCAAGUAGCUGGGACUACAGGCGCAUACCGCCAUGCCUGGCUAAUUUUUGUAUUUUUACUAGAGAUGAGGUUUCACCAUGUUGGCAAGGCUGGUCUCGAUCUCCUGACCUCAGGUGAUCUGCUCGCCUUGGCCUCCAAAAGUGCUGGGAUUAUAGGCAUGAGCCACCAUGCUGGGCGAGAUGACCUUUAAAAAACAUCAAGACAUGAGUGUGUACCUAGUAUCUGCUCAAUCAGAUACCACUACUAUGUAUAUGUAGAGUACCUUACAAUUUAUGAAGUAUUUUCCAUACUUCUCUCAUAUGACUCAUGAUUACCUUAUGAGGUAGGUUUUAUUACUGCCAUUUACAUUUGAAAAUAUUGAGGCUCAAGAGGCUGUUAAUUCUUCAGAGCCAUAGCUAGGAUCCAGUAACUGCUGUGCACAUUGCUGUCAUGUUUUAUGUAUCCAUCUAUAUGUACUAACUAUGUUAAUGGAAUAAUAAUUCUAUCAAAUAUAAUACAUUAUUUUUAUAUUCACAUUAUUUCUUGGUUUGUCUAAAUAUUGUCAUUCAUUGAUUCUAGUACUUAUGGUGUAUUUACCUGUGAAAGAAAAUGAUUAGAGAUUAACUUAAAAUGUUCAACACAGAAUAUGCAUAAAUGGUUGACUGUCUAAUUUUGCCUUGUGAAAUAAAAUCCAGCUUCACAAAAUAAAGGCCAAAAUUACCAGCCCUAUGA